GCUGUCGGUGAACACCACGGUGGAGGACGUGAAGCAAUAUUUUGAGCAGUUUGGGAAGGUGGGUUUAAACUGGGGGCGCUUGCUGCUGGGGCUGUGAACACACUGUAGAAUGGGGCACUAGCAAGCCGAAUCCAGCCAGGUCAUUCCAUUCCUGCAAAAGAUGAGAGUGGGGCUGGAUCCUGCUGUGGGGGCAGACCAGGCCAAUCCACCUUGCAGCCUCCUGGCUCAUCUGUGAGCUUCAGACUCAGGAUAUCCCUCGGGACAGAGAAGCCACACAGUAGCUGGCCCUGUUGUUGCCCUUCCACUGUAUUUUUCUCUUACUUAUCUUCAUUCUCACAAGGGAGGCAGUGCUCCCACAGCCAGUUCAAUCAAGUCAGCCCGUGGCCUCCUGGGAGUUUGCACCUGUCCAGGCCACAGGCUAUUGAACCUUUCCCCACUCCUUCCAGGCGAGGAUGAUAAGGAGGCAAUAAAUAUGACUCCCAAUUGCACUCGGCACCCUAUUUGCACAGGUGGGGAGCUUGGAGCCAGAGCUGGGGGGCUGCUGGUCCCCUGGGUAUUGGGGGGAACUGAUGAGAGCAUCCCCCAAUUCCUGAUCAGGCCCAGAGGAUUGGCUGUGAGCUGUAAGGGGCAUGGAGCUUUAAUUUCUGGGCCUCUGAAGAGGUAGAUGUUGUGGCGACAUCCGACAUUAGGGUGUCCUCUGAAAGGUGGACAAUGUGAACUUUGGAGUCCCAUGGGGAGAUGGCAGAGAGGGUCCUACGUUUGAAGUCUAGGAGGGAAAGAGGGUUGUUUUGCUUGGGGCCGGGGUCCCUGGUCUUUCUUCUUUUAGGUGAGACAGGCGAGAGGCUGGGUCUCUACUUUCCCAUCAAGACACUUCGAGUCACCCCCAGGCAAGCGAAGGGGGACGUGGCCUGGGAAAUGGGCCUGGGAUUGUGUGGGGGGGGGAGGUGUCCCCUGGCCAGCUGAGGCUGGUGGUGUGGGGGACCAGAGGCCUCGGCUUUCGUGCCUCGGUGGGCACCUGGGUCCGGGACAGAGGGCAGGUCGGGCGGGCCCGGGCCCCAGAGGGUAGGGCGCUCCUGGGAAGCAGCAGGCCCGGCUCGGCUGCGGCGGGGUGUCUUUGUGUCUGAGCGCCGAGCAUUAGAGCUCGCACUAAUCUGAUCCAGCAGCUGUGAUUGGAGGCCGCCUGCCCCCGGGGCCGGCGUUGCCAUGGCAACCGGGCCCCAGGAGAAGCCGUCAGCGGCCGCGUCUUUUGUUCGGGCCUAAAUCGGCGUUGGCAUGUGAAACCGGCCCGGGGAGGCCAGGGGGAGCCGGAGAAUAGGCUGCCAGGGAGCGAGGGGGACAGCCGGGAAUGCCAAGGGCCCCGCGGCGGGGGGCCCCCCGCCCGGAUCGAGGGGCCGCCGCCGAGGGGGGAACAAUGGUCAGCCGCCAUGGCUGCCACUCAGGCUUAGCGGCCGCCGAACUUGGCGGCUCGGCUCCUACUGGUGGACGACGCCAUGCUGAUGUUUGACAAAACCACCAACCGGCACCGAGGGUUCGGGUUUGUCACGUUUGAGAGUGAGGACAUCGUGGAGAAAGUGUGUGAAAUUCAUUUUCAUGAAAUCAACAACAAAAUGGUGGAAUGUAAGAAAGCUCAGCCAAAGGAGGUGAUGUCGCCAACGGGCUCAGCCCGGGGGAGGUCUCGAGUCAUGCCCUACGGAAUGGACGCCUUCAUGCUGGGCAUCGGCAUGCUGGGUUACCCAGGUUUCCAAGCCACAACCUACGCCAGCCGGAGUUAUACAGGCCUCGCCCCUGGCUACACCUACCAGUUCCCCGAAUUCCGUGUAGAGCGGACCCCUCUCCCGAGCGCCCCAGUCCUCCCCGAGCUUACAGCCAUUCCUCUCACUGCCUACGGACCAAUGGCGGCGGCAGCGGCGGCAGCGGCUGUGGUUCGAGGGACAGGCUCUCACCCCUGGACGAUGGCUCCCCCUCCAGGUUCGACUCCCAGCCGCACAGGGGGCUUCCUGGGGACCACCAGCCCCGGCCCCAUGGCCGAGCUCUACGGGGCGGCCAACCAGGACUCGGGGGUCAGCAGUUACAUCAGCGCCGCCAGCCCUGCCCCCAGCACCGGCUUCGGCCACAGUCUUGGGGGCCCUUUGAUUGCCACAGCCUUCACCAAUGGGUACCACUGAAGCAGGGGACGGUGGCAGGAGCGCCCCAGCCUGCAGCUGACUGAGGACCACGAGUGAGCCAGCGAGGGGGCGGGAGACCUCAGCCGCAGCCGCCGCCCCCUCCCCUGCAGCGACUCGGACCCGCUACUGCCUGCCCCCAACUCCCCGGGCCCGGCCCCUGCCCUGCUGCCCCCAACAGCGUCUGGCUCCCCUACUAACGUCCCCCUCUUCGCCCUUGCCCCCAUCCCCACCCGCCCCUCUCCCGGCCCUGCUUUUAUUUAUUUUGGAUUAGCCGGUUGCCCACCCCAGCCCUCUGGUCCAUCCCUCCCUCCGUGCCGCGCCCCCCUAGGACCGCCCCCUCCCCAAAAGGCUUUUGGAUUUGUGCAUAGCUGGAGUGAAGGCGGAGGGAGCCUGCUACAGGCCGCAGCCCAACCCCUGUUUUUUAUUCAGAUUUCCCCUCCUUUACCCUUUCCCUUUUUUUUUUUUUUUUUUUUUUUAAAGAAACCUUUUUUAAACUAUUUCUAGGUUUGUGAAUGUGAAGCCCCAGGCCGCAGGGGGCAAGGGGCCAGGUGCCCCCCACCAGCUGAGAACAAAGUGUCUAUCUGGGUGUGGGCCCCUGGCCGCCUCCCUCCAGCCCUGGAGAGGAGGGCAGGGCUGCGGGGAGGCCAGGCCGAGCCCCUGGAACCAUCCCGUCCUGUAUCAUAUGUAAAUACUGUGAGGUGAUGUGCCCACCCCUCUCUAAGACCCCUCGGGGGUGAGGGGCUCCCCCCUCCCCUGUUUCUGUCCCCUCAGACACCGUUACUGUAAGCUUGCAGGCCUCAGCUGUGGCCACGGCAGGCCCGCUCUCUCAGGCCCUCAGGGUCAAGGCCUUGGUUGGACCUGCCCACUCCAAAAACCCAGUGUGGGGGCAAAGGGCGUGGGAAGAGCAGGGCUUGCCCAGCGACACUGCUGGACAGGAAUUAACUCUCCAAAGGUCUCCCCUGCUCCCUACCUAGGUUGGGGCUUCAUGGUUUCUGCUCAGUCUGUCCCCCUUCCCCCUCGACCCCCGCAAUGAGUGGGCACCAGGGGACGCUCUGGCGAGGGCAGACCCCAGGGGAAAGCAAAGGGCGUCUCAGGGAACCCCCACAUUCUCUCACUGAAGUUUCCCACCAGGAUGACCCCACAGCCAGAGUCCCUUGGCAGCCCCUCACCCCAGACCCCCCUUCUAAGGAAAAAGAGAGGUUCAGAGCGUUGGACCUUCAUGAACAGUGGCCUGGCUGGCGUGGCAGGGCCAAGGCCCACCCACUGCCAUCCCCCUUCUGUGUGUCCCUCUCCCCCAGUUAUGAGGCCCAGGGCCUGAGCUCUCUUCCCCAGCAUUGCCCCCACCCGGAAACCCCACCUUUGGAGAGUUAAUUGUCUGUGUGAGGUGCUUAACCUAUCAGCCCUGAGAACACAAAGCAAUAAUCUUUGUUACUGAGAUGCGCGGCUGUUCGUGUUUUGGGUUUUUUUUUUUUUUAAUGUUUCCUAAUAAAAGAGAAGCUGCAUUUUAUUGGUUUUUAUUUUUAAUUUUCUACACGUUUGAGCUGAGUCCUGAGACACUUAGCUUCCCUCUCCCUCAUUCCCGGACCCUUCCACCCCACUGGGCCCAACCAUGGGCUCAGGACCCUGGAAUUCCGUUUUCUGAUUUGCUUUGGGAUUUUUUUUUUUUUUAAGAUGUUACAUGGUGUUUCGAAGCCAGCAAGUUACCAUCCUCCGGUGUCUCUUCUCUCCACAUCUGUAACUUCUUUUUCCAGGUUUUAUUUUCAGUUUUAAAUUCCUAAUAAAUUAUUUGAAAACGUU